GAAUGUGUACACGCCCAGCUUCCUGCCUGUUACUCUCCACAGUAUGCGAAGAAUAUCCCUGACUUCUAGCCCUGUGCGCCUUCUUUUGUUUCUGCUGUUGCUACUAAUAGCCUUGGAGAUCAUGGUUGGUGGUCACUCUCUUUGCUUCAACUUCACUAUAAAAUCAUUGUCCAGACCUGGACAGCCCUGGUGUGAAGCGCAGGUCUUCUUGAAUAAAAAUCUUUUCCUUCAGUACAACAGUGACAACAACAUGGUCAAACCUCUGGGCCUCCUGGGGAAGAAGGUAUAUGCCACCAGCACUUGGGGAGAAUUGACCCAAACGCUGGGAGAAGUGGGGCGAGACCUCAGGAUGCUCCUUUGUGACAUCAAACCCCAGAUAAAGACCAGUGAUCCUUCCACUCUGCAAGUCGAGAUGUUUUGUCAACGUGAAGCAGAACGGUGCACUGGUGCAUCCUGGCAGUUCGCCACCAAUGGAGAGAAAUCCCUCCUCUUUGACGCAAUGAACAUGACCUGGACAGUAAUUAAUCAUGAAGCCAGUAAGAUCAAGGAGACAUGGAAGAAAGACAGAGGGCUGGAAAAGUAUUUCAGGAAGCUCUCAAAGGGAGACUGCGAUCACUGGCUCAGGGAAUUCUUAGGGCACUGGGAGGCAAUGCCAGAACCGACAGGUAACUGAGCUGGGUGGGAGAAUGUGGCAGCUCCCUUUAAAGGUCAAAAGCCUUCCCUGUGUGGGUGUCAGUGUGUGUGUGCGAUAGAAAAUUUGAUUGACUUCUCCGUGGGCUUCCUGUCUGGAGAGUCAGUGAUGGCUAUAAGGAUUUCCCACCAUCCUCCCUUUCCCAUCCCACCUCCCACUGUUUCUUCCUCAGUGUAGAAACCCCUUCCCAUUAACCAAUGAUCCAGUCACAAUGACCCACUGCUAAAUGGUCCCAAGUCUAUCUGUGUCAUUGCAAACAUCCAGGCCUUCUCUUCCUCUAUUAUAAUUACCCUUCCACCAGCUCUAAUGCCACUUCUUAGGAAGCCUUCCCCACCUUCCCCACACAGAAUUAAGCACCACCCAUUGUGUCAUCCUCCAAACAGUUCUAACCACAGUAAUCGUGAAACUGUGUGGUAAUCAGAUGGAUAUUUGCUACCUCUCUCAGUAGAAAUCUGAGCUCCAUAAGGACAAGGCACAACCCCUAUUCAUCUUCAUGGCCCAGGGCCUGGUAGAGUGGCUGUCACAUGAGCCAGUGAUUAUGUGGGGCACCAUGUGUUCCUGGGGAAAGCAGGGGCUAAGGAAAGCAUAUUUUUAUGCUUUUUUUUUUUAUGUGACAGGGCUUGUGCUUUUUUUUCUUUUUUUUUUUUUUUUUAGUGUCACCAGUAAAUGCUUCAGAUAUCCACUGGUCUUCUUCUAGUCUACCAGAUAGAUGGAUCAUCCUGGGGGCAUUCAUCCUGUUAGUUUUAAUGGGAAUUGUUCUCAUCUGUGUCUGGUGGCAAAAUGGUGAGUGGCAGGCUGGUCUCUGGCCCUUGAGGACGUCUUAGUCUGGUAAGGACUCAAGAGAGGUGAAUCAUGGGUCUCAUCCAAGCCCCCGCUCCCUGAUCCAUCUCUCUCCACAGAAAUGGUGCACUGCCUUAGUCUUGAGCCCCCACACUACACAGCAGGGCUGGCAGCACAAUGUGCAGUGAGAGGAGGGAUGAAGCAAUCAUCUCCUCUCGAGGAGGGGCAAGGUCAAAGAUCUGGAACGCCUGCCUGGGGUGUUGUCUCCUUGCCAUCCGGCCCAGGUUUCAUCCAGCUCUUUGACGGAAAGUUUGUUUGCUGUCUGCGUUUACCGUGAUUUAGCUCAGCAGGUCCCAUCCCCUUUUCCCGUUCACCCUGAGAAGACUUGCUGGUGGCGCUUGUGGCUGCAGCAUUUACUCCCAGAUAACAUACAAGAUGUGGUAUAAGAAAUCCUUUCACCACCCUCUAAACAUUACAGUGCCGAACUACAUCCUACAUUUUUAGUAGAGAUGGGGUUUCUCCAUGUUGGUCAGGCUCGUCUUGAACUCCCGACCUCAGGUGAUGCUCCCGCCUCGGCCUCCCAAAGCGCUGGGAUUACAGGGGGAGCCAACACACCUGGCUGAGAGAACUAUUAUAUGCCAGACACAUUGCCAGACAUCUUCUGCUCUUUGGUCCUGUUUCUCCGCCACUGCUCUGACAUGAAGAAUUCAUUUCUUUCUUCCAUUGCUGUCUUUGUCCUCAUAGUGUCUUCUCUAAAUUGACCCAGGCAGACCUCAACAUUUUCAAGUACAGCAAUUUGGAAAAGUUAAGUAGAGCUCUAGGGUUCAAGUCACAGUUCCUGGGGCUCUCUCUGUGGAGUUCAAAGUUAGGAUUCCCUCUAAUGAGAAAAAUAGGCUACUCCAUCUGACUCACUGAGGAUCAAUGUUUCUGAUGUAAGAAAUGAUUCUACCCUUUUCAUUGCUUAAACGAAUACCAUGACUCAGAUAUGUGUCUGUUUUGCAGGGGCCCUGACAUGAAAAGUGAGUUUGCCAAGAUCGGUGUCACAACAGGCUUGGCAAGAUAUGGCUUGAGUCAGAUAAGGGCCACUGGUCCAGAAGGGGCUCGUGUGGUGGGUGGUGUGAUGGCAGCAGGAACCCAGGGAGUGAAUAUGCUGAGAUAGGAAGGGGUCCCACCCACAGAGCUGCAGGCAAAGGGGUCCCACCUUAAUCCCUGGUGGAAGGUGACUGAGAAGGACUUAACUGCCCCAACCAAGCAGGCUGGGACUUCAGUGCCAUUGACAAUAGUGAAGGGGAUUGGUGAGUAGGAAGGGAGGCAAAAGAACAGUUUUAGAAGCUGGGUCUGAACAGUAGGGAUUUAAAGGAGGUGGGACCUCCAUAGACACCUGGGAGUUCCUGGCCUCUAGCCUCAUCCUGGUAACCGAGUCGGCUGCUGAAGGGCUUCCUGUCUGGGCAGGAGCAGGCAGGGAUCAAGCGCCGGUGGAGGUCAGUGCCCACAGCUGAGCUGAACAGAAGUGGGAGGCAGAGUGGGCCUGGGGAAAGGUGUAUUACAAUUCAAGGGGAAAAAAAUAUAUCUGCCACCCUUUGGGGAGGGCCUCCCCACUGUGUCGCAUGGAUUUCUCUGUCACGGGGAAGAGCAGCACCCAGGGAAAAAGAGCUUUGUGUGCCCAUGACACAUUCCUAUUUUGUUGUCUCUGGCAUUUCUGGGCAUUGUUUCUGCUGAAGUGACAGAAGAGAGAAAAAGCUGAUCAAAGCUAAAUGACAGAGCAAAGGGGUUGACAGGGAGUGUCUUUUCAAAUACACAGGGACAUUCACCAAGAAGGGCCAUUUUUGGAUCAUAAAAUAAAUCUCAUCUGGGCGUGAUAGCUCACUCCUGUAAUCCCAGCACUUUGGGAGGCCAAGUUGGGUGGAUCAUUUGAGGUCAGGAGUUCGAGACCAGCCUGGCCAACAUGGCGAAACCCUGUCUCUACUAAAAAUACAAAAAUUAGCCGGGUGUGGUGGCAUGGGCCUGUAAUCCCAGCUACUCGGGAGGCUGAGACAGGAGAAUCGCUUGAACUCAGGAGGCGGAGUUUGCAGUGAGCUGAUAUUGCGCCAUUGCACUCCAGCCUGGGUGACAGAGUGAGAUUCCAUCUCAAUAAAUAAAUAAAUAAAUAAAUCUCAACAUAUGUAAAGGGUUAAAAUCAUGCGAAGCAUCUUGUCCAAGCACAAUGGAAAUAAACUAGAAAUCAACAGCAGGAAGCUAUCUGGAAAAAUCCUCAAAUGUUUGGAUAUCAAAUAAUAUGCUUCCAAAUAACUAUAUAUCAAAUUAAAAAGUACAAGGAAAACUAGAAAGUAUUUUGAAAUGAAUGAAAAUGAUAAUACAAAAUAUCAAAAUCUAUCAGACACAGAUAAGAAAAUGUCUAGAGGCAUCCACACUGAACUUUUUGAUCUCUGAAUCACCGUGCAUCAUUGCUGCCAAAUUUUUUGCUCAUGCUCAUCUCUGCCUGGAAUUUUCUUUCUUACCUGACCGAAUUCCAGACAGCUAUCCAAGUCCAGUUUAACUGUCACCUCCUCUAAGAAGUCACCAUUCUUCCUGGAUAGAAUUAACUACCCCCACUCGUAGCUCAGAAACUCUGACCACAGAAAAAUUAUCACAUUGUUUUAUGAUUGGGUGUAUGUCAGUAAAUUGAUGCGCUUACUUGAGGACAUUACUUUUGUAACCUGAGAAUCUAUCAUGGCUGCUAUAUAGUAGACGCUCAGGACAUGUGAGGACUUGAGUGGCAGCGGAGGUAAGGGUCAUCUCCUGGGUAUGGAGCUUGGACAAGAACCUGCACUCUUCUGUUCCAUUUCACCUCAACCAUCCAUGUCCCCAACCACAUCUCCACCAUCCUACCUGUACCAAGUGCUAAUCCUUUGAAUCAUGUCAGUGACUAUCUUCAGCUCAAUCCCAAUCACAGGUCAGGAGGGAGGGCAUCAGGUAUACUGUGAGCAAAACAGAGUAUGAGAUGGGGCCAACUGGCCUCUGGAUUAGGGGCAGGGCUUGUCCUGUAUGAGGACAGGGAGAAAUGAGGUUGCUAAGUCUCCCCAAGACCCCUGCCAAAUCUCACCAUAGACAUAAGAUGAGGUGAAUUUCAUUUAUCGCCUGGGCAUUCACGACCUGAGAGGCUUAGCUCUGGGUCAAGUUGAGCCCUCUCUGUCCCUGGCCAACAGGAGAAAGGCAAAGGCUGAAUGAGUCUCGGGGACUGUCUCUGCUUUGCAAGUGGGCCCUGAGGUGAACAGGGACCUUUCCAAAUUAAUGCAUCCACAGCGGUUUGGCAAAGUCGGGCUUUAAACCAGGGUCACUCUCCAGGGGUUGCCUAUGUGAUGGGUGGUCUGAUGGACAGAAACACAGAGGGUGGGCAAGACACAAUUUUGGGUGGGGCAGCAGCUUGAUGAUCUGACCAUCUGACCAUGGGAAAGUAUAUCACAUGCCAAAGGUUGAGGGGUCUCUAGGUUUAAUUCCUAGGAGGACAUAAUGAAGAAGGCUGCCUGGGCUCCAACAAAGCAGGCUGGAGGCAGGGCCACACAGACCGUGGGAGAGGGGAUUGUGAGCAGAAGGGAAGGCUGAAAGUGAACCCUAGACACUCUGUGAGGACAGCAAGGACUAGAAGGUGGGAUUCCUUUGACACCUGGGUUUCUGGUUCACCCCUGACACAGGAAUCCUGGCAAAUGGCGUCGUGCCAAGCCCCACCCUCAGUGCUCUGGACCUGCCGCAGGGAUACCCUUGCCCACAGCUGGAAGACUCUUGCCCCCGCUGUGGGCCUUCCCACUGUGUUCCCACUGAUACUUUGCCUUCCUUGGCUCUGAACCCCUAAAAUCUCUGCUGGGGUCUGGGUCUAACUAAUGAUGAAGUAACGGAAAGUGAACAAUCAUAAACUAGAUGACAGAGAGGCAGAAUGUGAACAAUAGCGGCUGAUCUCUCCCUGAGAGAGAGGUGGGAUCUGAGUCCUGAGAGAUCACGGAGGGGUCAAUCCUGAGCUGAUCUGACCCAGGGUUCUGCACUCUUUUGUCUCCUUCCUAAAGGCAGAAGAUCCACCUAGAGGUGAUACCACGGCGGCGCAGAGUUGUUCACCUGUGGUCCUCGAUCGCUGACAGCCUUGGCUCCCACUGCUGUGUGUUCCCUGAGUCAAGUGGAGGCGGAGCCUGCAAUGAGCGGAGAUCGCGCCUCUGCAUUCCAGUCUUGGCAACAGAGCAAGACUCCGUCUCAAAAAAAAAAAAUUUUUUUUCAGUACAUAUUUUUUAAAAGAUAGGGCUGGGCACAGCAGCUCACAUCUAUAAUCCCAACACUUUGGGAGGCCUAGGCAGGAGGAUCACUUGAGCCCAGGAAUCUGAAGCUGCAGUGAGCCUUUGCUCGUGAGAUUGUGGACCUAUGAUCCUACCACCAGCCCACCUGGUUCUAACACCCCCUCCUCUAUGUGUGAGAGGGAGAGAAGAAAAGUGAGGGAGAAAAGAGAGAUAAGCAAAGAACAGAGAGGAAAAAUGGAAAAUAAGAGGAAAUUGGGGGAAUUAAACAGAGGGGAGGGCAUGGAUCCCCGGGAGUUAGAAGAGUAGCAGCUUGUGGAUUACUACGCAGUGGAGGAAGAAGAGUUGUUGGAAAUUAUUUGAGAGGUAGUAUAAUCAUUUGUGAGGCAGUUUUCUGCAUUCACCAUUUCUCACAGACUAAGUUACUCAUAAGCAAACGUGCAAUUCACAUUACACUGAAAUUCUUCCCUAAUACAUCAUUUGCAUUGGAAUAAAGUACGGUUUUCAAACAACCUGAUAUAGCAGAACUGACUGUAUAAAUUAUGUGAGCACAGUGCAAGUAAUUCUUUGUUUGUUUGUUUGUUUUUUUGAGACAGAGUCUCACUCUAUCUCCCAGGCUGGAGUGUAGUGGUGCGAUCCCGGCUCACUGCAACCUCGAUCUCCCAGGCUCAAGCGAUUCCCCUGCCUCAGCCUCCUGAGUAGCUGGGAUUACAGGCAUGAGCCACCACGCCCGGCUAAUUUUUGUAUUUUUAGUAGAGACGGGGUUUCACCCUGUUGGCCAGGCUGGUCUCGAACUACGGACCUCAGGUGAUCUGCCCCCCUCAGCCUCUCAAAGUGCUGGGAUUAUAGCAUGAGCCACUGAGCCCAGACACAAGUAGUUCUUUCUGAUAAACACUUUAACACUGAAUGCAAAAAAAAAAAAAAAAUUGUGUGUGUACUUUUUUUAAUUUUACUUUAAAAUAGACACACCAAACAUGUUUCUAAAUAAAUGUAAUAUGGAAAUCUUUCUUUUUCUCCUCCAUUCUCAGUGAUGAUAUGGUUGUAAAUUCUUAUCAUCUGAUAAUUUUUAUCAGAUCUUUACAAAUUAUAAACUUAUUUGCAACUCUG